GCAUUUGCAGAGUGAGACAAAGCGGAGAACGCUGGUGGGCCUGUUGUGGAGUACGCUUUGGACUGAGAAGCAUCGAGGCUAUAGGACGCAGCUGUUGCCAUGACGGCCCAGGGGGGCCUGGUGGCUAACCGAGGCCGGCGCUUCAAGUGGGCCAUUGAGCUAAGCGGGCCUGGAGGAGGCAGCAGGGGUCGAAGUGACCGGGGCAGUGGCCAGGGAGACUCGCUCUACCCAGUCGGUUACUUGGACAAGCAAGUGCCUGAUACCAGCGUGCAAGAGACAGACCGGAUCCUGGUGGAGAAGGUACAGAGCGCUGCUGGGACAUCGCCUUGGGUCCCCUCAAACAGAUUCCCAUGAAUCUCUUCAUCAUGUACAUGGCAGGCAAUACUAUCUCCAUCUUCCCUACUAUGAUGGUGUGUAUGAUGGCCUGGCGACCCAUUCAGGCACUUAUGGCCAUUUCAGCCACUUUCAAGAUGUUAGAAAGUUCAAGCCAGAAGUUUCUUCAGGGUUUGGUCUAUCUCAUUGGGAACCUGAUGGGUUUGGCAUUGGCUGUUUACAAGUGCCAGUCCAUGGGACUGUUACCUACACAUGCAUCGGAUUGGUUAGCCUUCAUUGAGCCCCCUGAGAGAAUGGAGUUCAGUGGUGGAGGACUGCUUUUGUGAACAUGAGAAAGCAGCGCCUGGUCCCUAUGUAUUUGGGUCUUAUUUACAUCCUUCUUUAAGCCCAGUGGCUCCUCAGCAUACUCUUAAACUAAUCACUUAUGUUAAAAAGAACCAAAAGACUCUUUUCUCCAUGGUGGGGUGACAGGUCCUAGAAGGACAAUGUGCAUAUUACGACAAACACAAAGAAACUAUACCAUAACCCAAGGCUGAAAAUAAUGUAGAAAACUUUAUUUUUGUUUCCAGUACAGAGCAAAACAACAACAAAAAAACAUAACUAUGUAAACAAGAGAAUAACUGCUGCUAAAUCAAGAACUGUUGCAGCAUCUCCUUUCAAUAAAUUAAAUGGUUGAGAACAAUGCAUAAAAAAA